AGAGUGGCACGCGCUUUUUGCUUUUCCGCGUCUUCUUCGGUGGCGAUCCGCGUCCUAGAAAGGGCGGUGGGCUCCACCUCGGCCUAGAAGGCCAGCGGGAGCCGUAGGAAGCCGUCGCGGGAAGCUCAGCCGAAUUGGAGUUGGAGCCCCCGGAUUGCGCUGACCCUGAGCUCUCAGACUCCCCAGUACAAUGACUCAAGCAGAAAUUAAGCUCUGUUCUUUGUUGCUGCAAGAGCAUUUUGGAGAGAUUGUAGAAAAAAUUGGAGUCCAUCUGAUAAGAACCGGCAGCCAGCCACUAAGAGUAAUUGCCCAUGACACAGGAACAUCACUGGAUCAGGUGAAGAAAGCCCUGUGUGUCCUCGUCCAACAUAACCUGGUGAGUUAUCAAGUGCACAAACGUGGUGUGGUGGAGUAUGAAGCCCAGUGCAGCCGGGUAUUGCGAAUGCUUAGAUAUCCCCGGUACAUCUAUACUACCAAAACUCUGUACAGUGACACUGGAGAGCUGAUUGUUGAGGAGCUUCUGUUGAACGGCAAACUGACAAUGUCAGCUGUUGUGAAGAAAGUGGCAGACCGGCUCACAGAGACCAUGGAGGAUGGCAAGACCAUGGACUAUGCUGAAGUAUCAAACACAUUUGUGCGACUGGCAGACACACACUUUGUACAACGCUGCCCUUCGGUACCUACCACUGAGAAUUCAGACCCUGGGCCACCACCACCUGCCCCCACACUUGUCAUUAAUGAAAAGGACAUGUACCUGGUUCCUAAACUCAGCUUGAUAGGGAAAGGUAAAAGGAGGAGAUCAUCUGAUGAAGAUGCUGCUGGGGAGCCCAAGGCCAAGAGACCAAAAUAUACUACAGAUAACAAGGAGCCCAUUCCAGAUGAUGGGAUUUAUUGGCAGGCCAACCUUGACAGAUUCCACCAACACUUCCGUGACCAAGCCAUUGUGAGCGCAGUUGCUAACAGGAUGGACCAGACAAGCAGCGAGAUUGUGCGAACCAUGCUCCGAAUGAGUGAGAUUACCACUUCCUCUAGUGCUCCCUUCACCCAGCCAUUGUCUUCCAAUGAGAUCUUCAGAUCCCUACCUGUUGGCUAUAACAUCUCUAAGCAAGUUCUUGAUCAGUAUCUCACUCUGCUGGCAGAUGAUCCACUAGAGUUUGUUGGAAAGUCUGGCGACAGUGGUGGAGGAAUGUAUGUCAUCAACCUCCAUAAGGCAUUAGCAUCCCUAGCCACAGCCACUCUGGAGUCCGUCGUACAGGAGAGAUUUGGGUCUCGCUGUGCUAGAAUAUUCCGUCUAGUUUUGCAGAAGAAACACAUAGAGCAGAAGCAAGUGGAAGACUUUGCAAUGAUUCCUGCAAAGGAGGCAAAGGAUAUGCUAUAUAAGAUGCUCUCAGAAAAUUUCAUGUCACUCCAGGAAAUUCCCAAAACACCAGACCAUGCCCCAUCCAGGACCUUCUAUUUAUAUACUGUGAACAUCCUGUCAGCUGCCCGAAUGUUGUUGCACAGGUGCUACAAGAGCAUAGCCAACUUGAUAGAAAGGAGGCAAUUUGAAACCAAAGAGAAUAAGCGUCUACUAGAAAAAUCUCAGAGGGUAGAAGCCAUCAUUGCAUCUAUGCAGGCUACUGGUGCAGAGGAAGCACAGUUACAAGAAAUAGAGGAGAUGAUCACAGCUCCUGAACGUCAGCAGCUAGAGACCCUGAAACGUAAUGUCAACAAGUUGGAUGCCAGUGAGAUCCAGGUGGACGAAACCAUCUUCCUGCUGGAGUCUUACAUUGAGUGCACCAUGAAGAGACAGUGAUCCAGAAGAAGCAUCUUCCUCAGAAGAUCUGGGGGGAUGGAAAGCAAAAUAAAGGAGGUGCCUGGAUGCAUUAUUUGCAGUGGGAUAAGUCGCAGAGUCUUCAACUAAACCCCCCUCUCUAUCCCCUGCAGCCCAGGAUACACCUGAAAGAAUUUGGCAUAUUUAGAUCCAUUGCUGUAGUCUCCCCUCAUCAAAUCUUGGCAGUGGGAAGAACCUUAAAUCAACAAGGUUAAUCAUCUAUCAGAUGCAUCUGUUCCCAUAAAGAAGUUACCCACACCUAUGGUUACCUAUAUCCCUGGCAAUAGGAAACUUCCUAAGAAGUUAAUUUUAUUUUCAGAUGUCUAUGCCUGUUCUUUAUUUUGUUGAGAUAGGUGAUAGAUAGAUAGAUAGAUAGAUAAUUUGUUGUUGUUGAGACAGGAUCUCACUCUGUCACUCAGGCUGGGGUGUAAUAGCGCAAUCACAGCUCCCUACAGCCUUGACCUCCUGAGCUCAAGCAGUCCUUCCACCUCAGCCUCUGGAGUAGCUGGGACUACAGGCAUGCACCACACAUACCCAGCUAUUUUUUAUUUAUUUAUUUAUUUUUUUGUAGAGACAGGGCCUCCCUGUGUUGCCCAGGCUGAUGAACUGUAAUUUUUAACACACACAGUGUAGGGAAUGUGAAAGACUAUCACAGAGUAGAAGAAAAAAUUAUUUUCAGGGUUAGCAGGUGGAUUGUCCCAAGCAGUCACACUAGAAUCUGUGGACUGAAGCCACAUUUGCCAGCUCCAGGCUUCUAACACAUCUGAAACUGUGUAUGUAGAACAGCUAGCUCAAUGCCUGGCAUAUGGUAAGCACACAGUAAAUUAGCGCCUUCCUCUUCUCCAUGGUUCCUUAAAACUGGCAACGCUAAAUUCUCUCUCUCAGUAUCACGGAUAUAAUUUGUCCCAGCAGCUUUAAUUCAUUUAAAGCAGUUAGAUGUUUUAUAAUAUCUUCAGUUUUCUCUCACCAAUGUGUUUUCUAAUUGUUUAAACACUUGAGUGUCAAACAAUUGCCAGCCACCAUACUAAACACAACAUACAAGGAUAGAUAAAUAAGACACCAUCUCUGCCCUCAAGCCAGUCACCAUCAUUUACUAAGCACCUGUUUUGUGCUAAGUACUGGGGUAAGCCUUGGGGAUAUAAAGAUUAAUAAAUUUUGAGCAUACAGUCUAGUAGGAGGAGACAAAUAAGUACAUAAGUACCAGGAAGUAUUAGGGGUGCUACAGUAGAAGAGUAAACACUAUGUACAGAGAGGCCAGAAAGGGAAAAGGGUCAGGCAGGGAAGGGAACACAGAGAGUGACAAUGUAUAGUUUGAAAGAUGAGGAUGCUUUAUUUGCAAACUAUCUUAACAAGGGAUUCGUAACCAGAAUAUAUAAGGAGCUCAAACAAUAGCAAAAAGAACAAUCCAACUUAAAAAUGGCCAAAAGAUCUUAAUAGGUAGUUUUCGAAAGAAGAUACACAAAUGGCCGACAGAUACAUCAAAAAAUGUUCAACAUCACUAAUCAGAGAAAUGGAAAUCAAAAUCAAUGAGAUAACAUCUCACCCCAAUUCAUUACUUUUAUCAAGAAGAAAGAAUGAAUGCUAGUGAGGAUGUGGAAAAAGGAGAGCCCUGCCUGGUACACUGUUGGGAAUGUAAAUUGGUACAGCCACUGUGGAAGACUACAGAGGUUCCUCAAAAAACUAAAAACAGAACUAUGCUCCAGCAGUUCCACUACUGGGUAUAUAUAUAUCUCCAAAAGGAAAGAAAUCAAUGUAUCAAAAAGAUACCUGCACUCCCAUGUUUAUUGCAGCAGUAUUCACGAUAGCCAAAACAUGGAAUCAACCUAAGUGCCCAUCAAUAGAUGAAAGGCUAAAGAAAAUGUAUUAUUCAGCCAUAAGAAUGAAUGAAAUCCUGUCAUUGGCAGCAACAUGGAUGGAAUUGGAGGUCAUUAUGUUAAGUAAAAUAAACCAAGCACAGAAACAAA